GUCAAAGCUGAGCAGAGCAGGGAUGGGGAAGGUCUCCGGCCCCAGGCGCGGCGCGCGGGGCUUCUGCCCAGUUUCCUGCUUCUCAGCCGCGGUGUCUGCCCCGGCCCAGAGCAGUCUGUGCAAUUUAGAAACUCGAUAGGAGGCAGCAGCUGGUCUCCCACCACCCUAAAAAUAAUCCGUUCCGGCGCACUGCGUGCUUCGCCUAGGGGAGGAAAACUGUCAUCGGAGAGUUCUGCGUCCGGGUUUGAAAUUUACAUCUUAAGACAGUGUAGGAAGUCGGUGUUUUGAAGGUAGCUCAAGUGCACCGGCAGGGGUUUGAAGCAGCGUGAAGCUAUUGCCCAAGAGUAAACCAUAUAAGAAGAAAUGAGCCUUUCAUUUUGUGGUAACAACAUUUCUUCAUAUAAUAUCAACGAUGGUGUACUACAAAAUUCCUGCUUUGUGGAUGCCCUCAACCUGGUCCCUCAUGUCUUUCUGUUGUUUAUCACUUUUCCAAUAUUGUUUAUUGGGUGGGGGAGCCAAAGCUCAAAAGUACAAAUUCACCACAACACAUGGCUUCAUUUUCCGGGACAUAACCUGAGAUGGAUUCUUACAUUCGCUCUCCUGUUUGUGCAUGUCUGUGAAAUAGCAGAAGGCAUUGUUUCAGACUCGCGGCGGGAAUCAAGGCACCUCCACCUCUUUAUGCCAGCCGUGAUGGGAUUCGUUGCCACUACAACAUCGAUAGUGUAUUAUCAUAAUAUCGAAACAUCAAAUUUUCCUAAAUUACUUUUAGCCCUGUUCCUGUAUUGGGUAAUGGCCUUUAUUACAAAAACAAUAAAAUUGGUUAAGUACUGUCAGUCUGGCUUGGACAUAUCAAACCUGCGUUUCUGCAUCACAGGCAUGAUGGUCAUCUUGAAUGGGCUCUUGAUGGCUGUGGAGAUCAAUGUCAUUCGAGUCAGGAGAUAUGUAUUUUUCAUGAAUCCUCAGAAAGUAAAGCCUCCUGAAGACCUCCAGGAUCUGGGAGUGAGAUUUCUUCAACCAUUUGUGAAUUUGCUGUCAAAAGCAACAUACUGGUGGAUGAACACACUUAUUAUAUCUGCUCACAAAAAGCCUAUUGAUCUGAAGGCAAUUGGAAAAUUGCCAAUAGCAAUGAGAGCAGUAACAAAUUAUGUUUGCCUGAAAGAUGCAUAUGAAGAACAAAAGAAAAAAGUUGCAGAUCAUCCAAAUCGGACUCCAUCUAUAUGGCUUGCAAUGUACAGAGCUUUUGGGCGACCAAUUCUACUUAGUAGCACAUUCCGCUAUCUGGCUGAUUUACUGGGUUUUGCUGGACCUCUUUGUAUUUCUGGAAUAGUUCAGCGUGUGAAUGAAACCCAGAAUGGGACAAAUAACACAACUGGAAUUUCAGAAACCCUCUCAUCAAAGGAAUUUCUUGAAAACGCUUACGUUCUAGCAGUUCUUCUCUUCUUGGCUCUUAUUCUGCAAAGGACAUUUUUGCAGGCUUCCUACUAUGUAACCAUAGAGACUGGCAUUAACCUCCGUGGAGCUCUGCUGGCCAUGAUUUAUAAUAAAAUCCUUAGGCUCUCUACGUCUAACUUAUCCAUGGGGGAGAUGACUCUGGGGCAGAUCAACAACUUAGUCGCCAUUGAAACUAAUCAACUCAUGUGGUUUUUGUUCCUGUGUCCCAAUCUAUGGGCUAUGCCUGUUCAGAUCAUAAUGGGCGUGAUUCUGCUCUAUAAUUUACUUGGAUCAAGUGCAUUGGUCGGUGCAGCUGUCAUUGUGCUCCUUGCGCCAAUUCAGUACUUUAUUGCUACAAAGUUGGCAGAGGCUCAGAAAAGUACACUUGAUUAUUCCACUGAGAGACUCAAGAAAACAAAUGAAAUAUUGAAAGGCAUCAAACUUCUAAAAUUGUAUGCCUGGGAACACAUUUUCUGCAAAAGUGUGGAGGAAACAAGAAUGAAAGAACUAUCUAGUCUCAAAACCUUUGCACUAUAUACAUCACUCUCCAUCUUCAUGAAUGCAGCAAUUCCCAUAGCAGCUGUUCUUGCUACAUUUGUGACCCAUGCGUAUGCCAGUGGAAACAAUCUGAAACCUGCAGAGGCCUUUGCUUCACUGUCUCUCUUCCAUAUCCUGGUCACACCACUGUUCCUGCUCUCCACGGUGGUCAGAUUUGCAGUCAAAGCCAUCAUAAGUGUUCAAAAGCUGAAUGAGUUUCUCUUGAGUGAUGAGAUUGGUGACGACAGUUGGCGAACUGGUGAAAGUUCGCUUCCUUUUGAGUCCUGUAAGAAGCACACUGGAGUUCAGCCAAAAACUAUAAACAGGAAACAGCCUGGAAGAUAUCACCUGGACAGCUAUGAGCAAUCAACACGGCGUCUACGUCCCGCAGAAACAGAGGACAUUGCAAUAAAGGUCACAAAUGGAUACUUUUCAUGGGGCAGUGGUUUAGCUACAUUAUCCAAUAUAGAUAUUCGAAUUCCAACAGGUCAGUUAACCAUGAUUGUGGGCCAAGUAGGAUGUGGGAAGUCCUCUCUUCUCCUUGCCAUCCUCGGUGAGAUGCAGACAUUGGAAGGAAAAGUUCACUGGAGCAAUGUAAAUGAAUCUGAGCCUUCUUUUGAAGCAACCAGAAGUAGGAACAGGUACUCUGUGGCAUAUGCAGCUCAAAAGCCUUGGCUAUUAAAUGCUACAGUAGAAGAAAAUAUUACUUUUGGAAGUCCUUUUAACAAACAGAGGUACAAAGCUGUCACAGAUGCCUGUUCUCUUCAGCCAGAUAUUGACUUAUUACCAUUUGGAGAUCAAACUGAAAUUGGAGAGAGGGGCAUCAACCUGAGUGGGGGACAGAGGCAGAGAAUCUGUGUGGCACGAGCGCUGUAUCAAAACACCAACAUUGUCUUUUUGGAUGAUCCAUUCUCAGCCCUGGACAUUCACUUGAGUGAUCAUUUAAUGCAGGAGGGGAUUUUGAAAUUCCUGCAAGAUGACAAAAGGACACUCGUUCUUGUGACUCACAAAUUACAGUAUCUGACGCAUGCUGACUGGAUCAUAGCCAUGAAAGAUGGAAGUGUCCUAAGAGAAGGAACUUUGAAGGACAUUCAAACCAAAGAUGUUGAGCUUUAUGAACACUGGAAAACACUUAUGAAUCGGCAAGAUCAAGAAUUAGAAAAGGAUAUGGAAGCUGACCAAACUACUUUAGAGAGGAAAACUCUCCGACGGGCCAUGUAUUCAAGAGAAGCCAAAGCCCAGAUGGAGGACGAAGACGAAGAGGAAGAAGAGGAGGAAGAUGAGGAUGAUAACAUGUCCACUGUAAUGAGGCUCAGGACUAAAAUGCCAUGGAAAACCUGCUGGCGCUACCUGACAUCUGGAGGAUUCUUCCUGCUCAUCCUGAUGAUUUUCUCUAAGCUUUUGAAGCAUUCGGUCAUUGUAGCUAUAGACUAUUGGCUGGCCACAUGGACAUCGGAGUACAGUAUAAACAAUACUGGAAAAGCUGAUCAGACCUACUAUGUGGCUGGCUUUAGCAUACUCUGUGGAGCAGGCAUUUUCCUUUGCCUUGUUACAUCCCUCACUGUAGAAUGGAUGGGUCUCACAGCUGCCAAAAAUCUUCACCACAACCUUCUCAAUAAGAUAAUCCUUGGACCAAUAAGGUUUUUUGAUACCACACCCCUGGGACUGAUUCUCAAUCGCUUUUCAGCUGAUACUAAUAUCAUUGAUCAGCACAUCCCUCCAACCUUGGAAUCUCUAACUCGCUCAACACUGCUCUGCCUGUCUGCCAUUGGGAUGAUUUCUUAUGCUACUCCUGUGUUCCUGGUUGCUCUCCUGCCCCUUGGUGUUGCCUUUUAUUUUAUCCAGAAAUACUUUCGGGUUGCCUCUAAGGACCUCCAGGAACUUGACGAUAGUACCCAGCUCCCUCUGCUCUGUCACUUCUCAGAAACAGCAGAAGGACUCACCACCAUUCGGGCCUUUAGGCAUGAAACCAGAUUUAAACAACGUAUGCUGGAACUGACGGAUACAAACAACAUUGCCUACUUAUUUCUCUCAGCUGCCAACAGAUGGCUGGAGGUCAGGACGGAUUAUCUGGGAGCUUGCAUUGUCCUCACUGCAUCUAUAGCAUCCAUUAGUGGGUCUUCGAAUUCUGGAUUGGUAGGCUUGGGUCUUCUGUAUGCACUUACGAUAACCAAUUAUUUGAAUUGGGUUGUGAGGAACUUGGCUGACCUGGAGGUCCAGAUGGGUGCAGUGAAGAAGGUGAACAGUUUCCUGACUAUGGAGUCAGAGAACUAUGAAGGCACAAUGGAUCCUUCUCAAGUUCCAGAACAUUGGCCACAAGAAGGGGAGAUCAAGAUACAUGAUCUGUGUGUCAGAUAUGAAAAUAAUCUGAAACCUGUUCUUAAGCACGUCAAGGCUUACAUCAAACCUGGACAAAAGGUGGGCAUAUGUGGUCGCACUGGCAGUGGGAAAUCAUCGUUAUCUCUGGCUUUCUUCAGAAUGGUUGAUAUAUUUGAUGGAAAAAUUGUCAUUGAUGGGAUAGACAUUUCCAAAUUACCACUGCACACACUACGUUCUAGACUUUCAAUCAUUCUGCAGGAUCCAAUACUAUUCAGUGGUUCCAUUAGAUUUAAUUUAGAUCCAGAGUGCAAAUGCACAGAUGACAGACUCUGGGAAGCCUUAGAAAUUGCUCAGCUGAAGAAUAUGGUCAAAUCUCUACCUGGAGGUCUAGAUGCGGUUGUCACUGAAGGUGGGGAGAAUUUUAGCGUUGGACAGAGACAGCUAUUUUGCCUUGCCAGGGCCUUUGUCCGCAAAAGCAGCAUUCUUAUUAUGGAUGAGGCAACAGCUUCCAUUGACAUGGCCACAGAGAAUAUUUUGCAAAAAGUAGUAAUGACAGCCUUUGCAGACCGGACCGUGGUGACAAUAGCUCACCGUGUCUCUUCUAUUAUGGAUGCAGGCCUUGUUUUAGUCUUUUCUGAGGGUAUUUUAGUGGAGUGUGAUACUGUCCCAAAUUUGCUCGCCCACAAGAAUGGCCUCUUUUCCACUUUGGUGAUGACCAACAAGUAGACCAUCAUGAUCUAUUGCACCAAGUCUGUCAUUCUCCGCAUCGAGUACACACUAUUCUGACGGCAGACCUGGUUAUUGUGAUGAAGCGAGGAAAUAUUUUAGAAUAUGACACUCCAGAAAGCCUCUUGGCUCAGGAAAAUGGAGUAUUUGCUUCUUUUGUUCGCGCAGACAUGUGAAGGAGUGUCUUAAAACAAUACAUGUAUUUAAAAUAAUGCAGUCAUAACCUAAUUAAUGGAUCAUCAGCUUGACCUCUGUAAAGUGGCAUCUUAAAACUUUUACAGAUUUUUGCACAAAAAGUGGACAUUUAUUUUUCCUGUUUUUAAAACAGUUUUUCAAGAUAUUAUUGCUUAAUAUGUUCAUUAUUGAUGUUUUUAUAGUGAUCCAGCCACUCUAGCUUUAAGAAUAGCUAGGUUGUAUUAAAACAUGUAAGCUACUUUAAGUGAUAAAUCAAUAGCUAAAGUUUUCUCCUAACUUUAAGUCUGGUAAAUAUCUCUCAGGAAUGGAAGUGUCAAUGAGUAGUCAGUAUUACUAUACUCUUGUUUGUAAGAAUAUAUUUUCCUUAUUGUUGGAGUCUCCAGAGGUUAUUGGAAGGAAUAAAAAAGGACAUGUUUUCUAACGAAACUCUCAAAUUCAUUAUCUACUUCAUGAGAAUUUAUUUGUAUUCAUUAACAUUAGUAAUACCUAUUUUUCUUAAGAGCCUUCUUUUUUCCCUUUUGUUUCUUGUCACCAAGAAGUUAUCACACUUAUACUUAUUCUAUAAGGCCAAAGCCUUAUCUAGAAAGAUCAUGAAGAGUUUGGAUAUUUUUAAAACUAUACUCGAAUUUUCAUUUUUUCCUGUCCUGUAAAGAGAGAAUUCUUAAGAUAUCAGGCAUAAUGUAUGUACCUUUUCCAGACUGAAGUUCAAAGAAUGAUUAGGUUCAAUCUUUCAGUGGCAGGCCAGCUAAACUUUCUAUAGUUUAAUGAUUAGCUGUGGUUAUGAUCUUGAGCCCUAACAUGCCACAUUACUCAAGAUUUACACAGGCAAGUGACUUCAUUUGGCACUGCUAAUAAUGGCAGGUGAACAUUCCUCUCAGGUGUGAGAUAUUUCCUAUGAAACAGUCCACUGGCAGGCUGGAGAUAUCUUACACUUUGAAGUUAUAUAUAUAUAAAACAAGUGUCUAUUUCUAGCUGAAAGAGUUUACCUCUUCUAGACAUUUAUGCCCAAUGGUGUCACACAUGAUCAUUUGCUCCUGCUCUAAUUUUAAUGUGCAUACAAAAAAUAUACCAAAAAUGUUAUUGUAAUUUUAAUGAGCAUGUAAAGAGUGUAUCAAAAAUUGAUGGGAUAUUAGUGUUAGGUUUUGCUUAAAUGAAAAUUAAUAAAUUCAAAAAUACUAAAAGUCACCUUCUUUGUCACGUUAGCAACCAGUUUCUACUAUUCUGUGCCCAUCCAGUGUCAAUAUCAUUGAUUUCUUUUUCAUAUGAAGAUCCACAUGCAUUGUAAGAUUGUGAAGAUAUAUAAAAUUGAUGAAUUAAGAGAAAUUAUGCCACUUUCCUAUAGUUUCUGUGUUCUGUUUAUUGUAUGGUGUAUUCACUCUUGGAAAAUAUGUAAUAGUUGUGUAUCCAGAAUAUGUGUCUUCACCUGAAUAUUUAAUCUUUAUAUUUACAAAAAAAUAAGUUCCACAAGAUGGACAAAAAUGGUCCAUGAUAUUUAGCUUAAAUUGUAACCUUUUGUUGUGUAUAUAAAACUUCCUUGGAAGAAAAUAACCUUAUUGUUUUCUUAAAGCUAAACAGAAUAGGAUUGGUACUCAUUAAUUAUGUCUUGCAAAUAUUUUCUAAAAAUUCAACCACUCUCCUAAAAUGGUGUUUAAAUAUUUUGUAGGGCAGAAUAUGCAUAUUGCCUGUUAGCAAGUAAUAAUUCAUUCUCAUAGAGAAAUGGGUUUUUACCCAUGGAAGUAAUCUUUUUUUUUUCUUUUUUUUUUUUAAUUUUUUUUUUAAUAUACUUUAAGUUUUAGGGUACAUGUGCACAUUGUGCAGGUUAGUUACAUAUAUAUACAUGUGCCAUGCUGGUGCGCUGCACCCACUAACUCGUCAUCUAGCAUUAGGUAUAUCUCCCAAUGCUAUCCCUCCCCACUCCCCCCACCCCACCACAGUCCCCAGAGUGUGAUAUUCCCCUUCCUGUGUCCAUGUGAUCUCAUUGUUCAAUUCCCACCUAUGAGUGAGAAUAUGCGGUGUUUGGUUUUUUGUUCUUGCGAUAGUUUACUGAGAAUGAUGGUUUCCAGUUUCAUCCAUGUCCCUACAAAGGACAUGAACUCAUCAUUUUGUAUGGCUGCAUAGUAUUCCAUGGUGUAUAUGUGCCACAUUUUCUUAAUCCAGUCUAUCAUUGUUGGACAUUUGGGUUGGUUCCAAGUCUUUGCUAUUGUGAAUAAUGCCGCAAUAAACAUACGUGUGCAUGUGUCUUUAUAGCAGCAUGAUUUAUAGUCAUUUGGGUAUAUACCCAGUAAUGGGAUGGCUGGGUCAAAUGGUAUUUCUAGUUCUAGAUCCCUGAGGAAUCGCCACACUGACUUCCACAAUGGUUAAACUAAAGAGCUUCUGCACAGCAAAAGAAACUACCAUCAGAGUGAACAGGCAACCUACAACAUGGGAGAAAAUUUUCGCAACCUACUCAUCUGACAAAGGGCUAAUAUCCAGAAUCUACAAUGAACUCAAACAAAUUUACAAGAAAAAAACAAACAACCCCAUCAAAAAGUGGGUGAAGGACAUGAACAGACACUUCUCAAAAGAAGACAUUUAUGCAGCCAAAAAACACAUGAAAAAAUGCUCAUCAUCACUGGCCAUCAGAGAAAUGCAAAUCAAAACCACUAUGAGAUAUCAUCUCACACCAGUUAGAAUGGCAAUCAUUAAAAAGUCAGGAAACAACAGGUGCUGGAGAGGAUGUGGAGAAAUAGGAACACUUUUACACUGUUGGUGGGACUGUAAACUAGUUCAACCAUUGUGGAAGUAAUCUUUUAAUGAUAUUUUCUUAUUAUAUUGCUACAGGCAACAUCAGUAGAAGCCUAUCUAGUUACACUAAACUAAAGAUCACAUUCACCAUUCUUACAGCCAAGUGGUUGCUGGUCCCCUCAUAACUUUUAGUUACUUAAGUUGAGUAAAUGUCUAAUUGUUUACAAACUAAAUUGACUAAAUAAGGUCAAGGAUAAUGUUUUUCAUUGAUUAACCAUUUAUUAUACAUAUAAUCUAUUGAAUAUAAAAAGAUUCACCUUGAAAUAAUAUUUGACUAUAUAGGUACAUAUCUGUAAAAGAUGACCACCUUAACUAAAUCAGAUUUUACAUUUAUAAAUUUUAUAUUUAAUUAGUCAAAUCAAUUUUUAAAUCAUAACUCCUUAAUCUCAUAAGAAGCAAUAAAUGCAUAAAGCAUUAUAUUAAAAUACCAGGGUUACUUAUGUCAUUGACAGGGAAAAGACUUUGUAUAAACAAUUAUGCACCAUCUAUUUUUGUACUCUUACUCAUGAUCCAUUUAAAAGUCUACUCAGCUCUAGAUUAGAUACCAGAAGACCCUCUAAGUAACUGAUAACUGAGAUUCGGGACCAUGUCUUGUUUGCCAUUGUGCCCUUGGAAUUUAAUACAAGUGCCUAACCCACAGUAGGGUUGAUUGAUUCACUGAUUAGUUUUACUGCCAUGUGCCUAUAACUAUAGGUUAUUCUCUUUCCUUUUCUAUGUUGUGUUUAUUCUAUUUAUUCUCUACAAUAUAUAAAAUGUAUUUGUUCUCUACAAUAAAUGUGUUUAUUCUCUACAAUAUAUAAAAACAUAUUGGACUACUAUUACAUAAUUAAAUUACUCUUUUAUUUGCUUAAA